CACUCUGUUUUGCAGAAAAGAUUCUGUGGAUUAAUACAGAAGCACCAGCAACACCAGAGGGGUGGAGACUCCUUUCUCUCCCGAUUCUACAGUCUGGCUCUAAGCCCAGUAAAACAGCUCCCGAGCACUGCUUCAGCUGGGUCCAGUCUUGACAAAGGCAGGAAGCCAGCUAGGGUGGGGGCGAUAGGGUCAGCGGGUAUGUCCCACUGUUGGAGGUCACUGGUAUUCUGUUUGUUUUUGUUUUGUUUCGUUUUGUUUUUUGAGACAGGGUCUCGUUCUGUCGCUUAGCUGGAGUGCGGUGGCGUGAUCAUGGCACUGCUAUUCUUGAAGCACUCCACCCACCUGGGCUACUUUUUCUUUAGUGCAGAGGUGCACUGUCUUCUUUUAGGUGGGAUCGCGUAAGCAUGAGCUGGUAGAGCACGGAGAGGCAGGCAGCCAGGUUACGAAGACUAAGCCAAUUAUUCACUGAAGUCAUCCUCCUCCCCCCCACCAUUCGAUUUGAUCUACCUCUAAGCCAGGCUGUGAAGAAAAGGAAGGCACUUUAGAAGACCUCAGCAGUGUGGUUCUGUGUCUACUUCCAUGACCUGUACCUGAGUAUCUUAGCCAGCCAGCCUUAGGAACACCACCAAGGUUACUUUGAAAUCUAUGUAUAUAGCUAGUUACAGACGGGAGCUAUGUGUUUCUUCAUUAUUUUGCAGCUCCUCGUUGUUCCUGUGAUUCCUGAACACCUUUUUGGAAAUAUGGGUCUCUGUGAGUUUUGAGCACACUACUAUCACUUUGGAUAGUCACUCCAUUUAUAUUUUUAUAAACUUCCAUUAGAGAAUCAUUAAGGCUGUUUAAUAUCUGCUCUGGAUAUUACGCAUUGGCUUUUUGUUGCCUAGUGCUACAAACCUUCCUGUGGGACUCAGUGUCUUCAGGCAAUGAUUGUGUAUCCUGUUACAGAUGGUUGUGAUACAAGAAGAACCACUCUUCUUUGAAAAUAAACUCUUGGAAGCUUUUGCCAGCUAUUUGGGGGGUAGGAGGAAUAUUAGCAACUGUAUUGGUUGUCUACAGAUACAGAAUUGCCUGUUGUGAGGGAACUGAUUGUUUUGUUGGGAAAAGAAAUUUACCAGGAGAAAGAGUUUUGUGCUGUAUUGUGAGAGAUCUCGCCUCUCAGUUAAAUGAGCCCUGGGUUAAAGUCAGUGUGAAGGGCAGCUGUGUGCGGGCACGAGCCAGAGUGUCUGCCUCAGACUAGAUUUGACUUGAGUUCUUUAUGACCCAGGACUCUGGAUAAUGUGAAUUUGCUUUCCUAUUUAACUAGAAGAUACAUGUACUAUAGAUCAUUGUCUCAUUUUAGUGAUUGUUCCUUAAACUAGUGAAACUAGUGGAUUUCUCUUCUUCCUCUUUAUUUUCUGCAUGUUAAAUGUGAACCUUAGUGUAUUUGUAUUUUGUAGAAAAUAAUGAAAAAUUUUAAUGGAGAAUGAUUUAAAAACAUUUACAAUACAUUAUUUUUGCAUCUGU